AGUAUAUUCUUGCAGCACAUAACAGUACUUGUUUCUCAGACAUAAGUUUUUAUAUUAUGAGCACUCUUGGCAAGUUGGCCUAUUUCAUUUAGGUCCAGCCUAGUUAUAUGCCUGUGCUAAAUAAAAAGGUUGCUCUAGAAUGGCCUAUCUAGUGGUUGCUGUGUAAAGACAUGUUAUCUUAGCUGUAUAGUCAUUUAAAAUAUUGAUCUAGAAGAACUUAGUGCAUGGGAAAAUGUUCAGUUUAUAAAAUAGAGGAAAAAGUAGUUAUCAAACUUCAUGUCGAAAAUCUUAGCUUUGUAAAGAACUGUUAAGUAUAGAGGAUGUACACUCGGACCUGAUGAGAAGUCAUCAUAGAUGAGCGUAUAGGUGAUUUUUACUUUCUUCUUUGUGCUUUUAUGCAUUUUCUAAACUUUCUAAAGUGAAAGUCUUGUAUUAACUUUUCCAGCUUGUUUUUUGGAGAGAAGUAUUGUGAAAAUAGUUACAAAUCUCUUUUUACCCUGACAUCCCCCCAAGCCCGAAAAAGAAGCAACUAACAAAACACUGUGAUAAUAAGGAUUAUUCAGUAUGCAGUUUGCAGGAUAUCCAUGACGACAUUGAAAAUGAAUUUUUUGUAUUCACCAGAUAUUCUUAUAUGAGAAGAUCUAUUUUAAACAGUCUAAAUAUUUUUUCUUCUGUUGGACCAGCAUGGCAGGAUUUAAGCGAGGGUAUGAUGGAAAGAUUGCUGGAUUAUAUGAUCUGGAUAAAACCUUGGGUCGAGGCCAUUUUGCCGUGGUUAAACUUGCCAGGCAUGUCUUUACGGGUGAAAAGGUGGCAGUAAAAGUUAUUGACAAGACAAAACUGGACACUCUAGCUACUGGUCAUCUUUUCCAGGAAGUGAGAUGCAUGAAACUAGUGCAGCAUCCUAACAUCGUCCGCCUUUAUGAAGUUAUUGACACCCAGACCAAACUAUAUCUUAUUCUAGAACUUGGGGAUGGAGGAGAUAUGUUUGAUUAUAUAAUGAAACAUGAGGAGGGUCUUAAUGAAGACUUGGCCAAGAAGUAUUUUGCUCAGAUAGUUCAUGCUAUAUCUUAUUGCCAUAAACUCCAUGUGGUUCACAGAGACUUAAAACCAGAGAAUGUAGUCUUCUUUGAAAAACAAGGUCUUGUAAAGUUGACAGACUUUGGGUUCAGCAACAAAUUUCAACCAGGGAAGAAGCUCACUACAAGCUGUGGAUCUCUUGCAUAUUCCGCUCCAGAAAUUCUGCUUGGUGAUGAGUAUGAUGCACCUGCAGUAGAUAUUUGGAGUCUGGGAGUGAUCCUUUUCAUGUUGGUGUGUGGGCAGCCGCCCUUUCAAGAAGCCAAUGACAGUGAAACACUGACAAUGAUCAUGGAUUGCAAAUAUACAGUACCAUCCCAUGUGUCUAAAGAGUGUAAAGACCUAAUCACACGGAUGCUACAGAGAGAUCCCAAGAGAAGGGCUUCUUUAGAAGAGAUUGAAAAUCAUCCUUGGCUUCAGGGAGUGGACCCUUCACCAGCUACAAAGUAUAACAUUCCCCUUGUGUCAUACAAAAAUCUCUCGGAAGAGGAGCACAACAGCAUCAUUCAGCGCAUGGUGCUUGGGGACAUAGCGGAUCGAGACGCCAUUGUAGAAGCCCUGGAAACCAACAGGUAUAACCAUAUCACAGCCACAUACUUCCUGCUGGCUGAAAGGAUCCUGAGAGAAAAGCAAGAGAAAGAAAUACAGACCAGAUCUGCAAGCCCGAGCAAUAUCAAGGCCCAGUUUAGGCAGUCAUGGCCAACCAAAAUUGAUGUACCCCAGGACCUUGAGGAUGACCUCACGGCCACUCCUUUGUCCCACGCGACUGUCCCUCAGUCUCCUGCUCGGGCUGCUGACAGUGUCCUCAAUGGCCACAGGAGCAAAGGCCUGUGUGACUCAGCUAAGAAAGAUGACCUCCCUGAGUUGGCUGGACCAGCACUCUCUACGGUGCCACCCGCAAGCUUAAAACCCACAGCCAGUGGGCGGAAGUGUCUGUUCAGGGUGGAAGAAGAUGAAGAGGAAGAUGAGGAGGACAAGAAACCCAUGUCCCUCUCAACACAAGUGGUUUUGCGCCGGAAGCCAUCUGUAACCAACCGCCUGACAUCCAGGAAGAGUGCGCCCGUCCUCAACCAGAUCUUUGAGGAAGGGGAAUCUGACGAUGAGUUUGACAUGGAUGAGAAUCUGCCUCCCAAGUUGAGCAGGUUAAAGAUGAAUAUAGCUUCUCCAGGUACAGUUCACAAACGCUACCACCGGAGGAAAAGUCAGGGCCGGGGCUCCAGCUGCAGUAGUUCGGAGACCAGUGAUGAUGAUUCUGAAAGCCGGCGGCGGCUCGAUAAAGAUAGCGGGUUCACCUACUCCUGGCACCGACGGGAUAGCAGCGAGGGGCCCCCUGGCAGUGAGGGGGAUGGCGGGGGCCAGAGCAAGCCAAGCAAUGCCAGUGGAGGGGUGGACAAGGCCAGCCCCAGUGAGAACAAUGCUGGUGGGGGCAGUCCCUCCAGCGGCUCGGGUGGCAACCCCACCAAUACAUCGGGUACCACACGCCGCUGUGCCGGCCCCAGCAACUCCAUGCAGCUGGCCUCUCGCAGUGCUGGGGAGCUCGUUGAGAGCCUCAAACUCAUGAGCCUCUGCCUCGGCUCCCAGCUUCAUGGGAGCACCAAGUACAUUAUUGAUCCACAGAAUGGCUUGUCAUUUUCCAGUGUGAAAGUCCAAGAGAAAUCUACGUGGAAAAUGUGCAUUAGCUCCACAGGGAAUGCAGGGCAGGUCCCUGCAGUGGGCGGCAUAAAGUUUUUCUCUGACCACAUGGCAGAUACCACCACUGAAUUGGAACGGAUAAAGAGCAAGAACCUGAAAAAUAACGUGCUGCAGCUACCUCUGUGCGAAAAGACCAUCUCUGUGAACAUCCAGCGGAACCCUAAGGAGGGGCUGCUGUGCGCAUCCAGCCCAGCCAGCUGUUGCCAUGUCAUCUGACUGUGGCCCCAUCUGGCCGCUAGCACGCUUCCUGCUCAGAGCAGUGAAGACCGGCUCACUUCACUGUUCCAUUUGGUUUUACUAUUUUAAAGUGGGCGUUAGGAGCAAUUAUUUAUUACCUUUCCAUUUGUUCGCCUGAUGAUGUGACAAUGCAUGGUCUUUGUGCAUGCUGCUAGACACUUUUCUUUCCCAGCCGAAAAGCCUAUUAUGUAAUUUUUACAUUCAUAAUUUUAAUGUGGAUGAUCAGGAUUAAAUCAAGAUAUAUAUCUGGAACCUCUUAUAAAUGGAGCACUUAGAAAUUUGUUGUUCUGCACUUAACCUAGAGAGAGAAAAAAUGCUUUUCUUUGUGAAAAAUCUGAAUUCCUGUCCUGACCUUCUGUGAUGUGGAAACCCUAGGCUCUGAGACACACUCUCUGGUGUCUGAGACAGAACCAAAGCAAUAACGUUGUGAUGCCCACAGGCCUGGAGCCAGCUAGCGACCUUGUGCCGCCCAGCUGUCCAUGGCCCGUGCAGAGCAGAGGACAGUGAGUGUCUGCACUGAGAACCUUAAACCACAGUUGAACAUACCCACACCUGUUUGUCUUAAGCUAUAGUGUAAAAACAAAGUUUGGGCUCUGAAAAUUUAACUGAAAAAGAUUUCCUUGUUUUUGUAAUAGGUGAGAUAAAGUACUUAGAUUUAUAAGGCAGCUUCCCCUGUAGUGAUAAAUUACAAGCAGACAAUCUUAUUUUGUAAUGUGAUGAAGUGAUGAUGUCUUAACUCUACUUAGAGAGUGUAUGUCUGUCUAACAGAACAAAAAGAUGCUCUGUGUAAAUUCCUUCCUGUAGGGCACACUGCAGGAUUUCCAUGUAGAUAGAAGAACUAUAGGGCCUAGUACAGAAGGUGCACACAAAUGUUGGCAAAGUCAAAACCCCAUGAAUUAAAACCUACUGGAAUUUGGUUUUUAGGAGUUUGGUAAUUAGAUUAUCUCUUUUGUUAUUUUCAUUCAGUUAUAUCCUUUGGCUCAGCUAGCUUUGAAAUUGGCUGAUGAAAAAAUAUACAUAAAAGGGUAAAAUUCACACAUACAGCAAACAAAAAUGCACAAAGCCUGCUUCGUAACUUUUUUUUCUGGAAUUGUUUUUCACUUUGCCUUUUUCUGCCAAAACAAUAAUCAAAGAACUCUUGCUUUAACCUAUUCCUGUACAAAGACUGUUUUUGACCAGAUAAUCAUCUGUUGUGGCAUUCUAUCUUGUAGGACACUGUAUAUUGCAAAUUGCUGAUUAUGGAAGGGGCCAGUUGCUGUUUUUUCAUGCAGUGCCCUGGGAGUCUUAAAAGCAGUGCUUAGCAACAUUGGUGAUAGCAUGUGGCUGGGACCCAGGGCCCUUCCCCACUCUUCAGCCCCGAGUCAUGUGUCUGAGGUGACGGACUGAGACGCAUCUGGUCCUGUAAUUCAGAGAGUGGGCACAUCACCAAAGAACUGCAUUGCUGUGGUCACUGUUUCUUCAAGUACACACUGACUCUGCUACUUUAGGAUAAAUAUAUUUUACUCAGAACUCUGAAUUUCACAGUAUACUUACUAAACUAAGUAAAAAUGAUACUUAAAAUACUUAUUUUACUUUCUAGACCUAGGCUAGAUGUUUUAAGCUACAGCUCUAGUUCAUUGUGAUAUUUAUAAUUUGAAAGCUAUGAGAAUAGAUGUGUGGGUGAAGCCAUAGAACAUAUUUGCUUGAAAUUCUUGAGCAGGGAUCUUAUAAAGGGCCAGAAAUAAGAUGUGUGGUUCACAUAGAUAGUGAGCGUAACAUCUGUAUUAAACAUAGGAGAGAAGUUUAUAAAGGGCAUUGGCAAUAAACUCUUUGUUGCAGCUGUUUUCCAAGCAGUGUAAAUACUUUUUCCUGUGAUUAUGUAUAGCCUUGGAAUGGCACCUUUUAACUAACCCAUAUGUGUUUGGUUUCAAUGGUUUUUUAUAUUCAGAUGUAUAUAUGGUGCUCACUUUAGGAUCAGCAGUGUUGACCAUUUAUGCUGCAUAGCUGUAUUAUAGCCUUAUUAGUUGUGUGGUUGACCCUUGGGGUAUACAAAUGUCAGUCUGAGUGGUGUCUUACUCCUUUGUUUAUAAGUGAAUGAUUGUGCAUGUUUUGUAUGUCAUAGUAUGUCGUCACAUAAAAGGGAGGGAGCGAAAAACCAUUACAUUAAGAUAAUAUUGGACCAAACUACUUACUUGCUCUAAACAGUUACUUGUACCCCUUAACCUGUCUUCAAAAGUUGCAUAUAGUUACAGUAGUGUAUAAAUUAAAUAUUGUGGAAAAACAGUCUUGUAUUUUUCUGUAUGUGUGUAUAUAUAUAUAAUUAUGUACUUCUGGCAAUUCUAUCUGUAUUUAAAGAUGUGACAAUCUUGACACCAAUUUUAAGAAUAGCUGUGAGACCGAAUUAAAGAUAAUCCCUACCAAGUGAAAAUUGAUGUGUGUUAAGAGGGUACAGAAUUAUCAACUGAUUUGGUCAGUUGCUUCCAAUGCUGGUUGAUUUCCCUCAUUGUGUAAACAUUGACAGGUAUGUGACAAAUGGGAAAAAAAAUCCAAAUAAUAAAGUGACAUAUUGGUGUUCAGCAAUAUAAA